ACAUUCACUACACCUUUUCCAUUUGCUAAUAAGGCCCUGCCAGGCUGGGAGGGAAUUGUCCCUGCCUGCUUCUGGAGAAAGAAGAUAUUGACACCAUCUACGGGCACCAUGGAACUGCUUCAAGUGACCAUUCUUUUUCUUCUGCCCAGUAUUUGCAGCAGUAACAGCACAGGUGUUUUAGAGGCAGCUAAUAAUUCACUUGUUGUUACUACAACAAAACCAUCUAUAACAACACCAAACACAGAAUCAUUACAGAAAAAUGUUGUCACACCAACAACUGGAACAACUCCUAAAGGAACAAUCACCAAUGAAUUACUUAAAAUGUCUCUGAUGUCAACAGCUACUUUUUUAACAAGUAAAGAUGAAGGAUUGAAAGCCACAACCACUGAUGUCAGGAAGAAUGACUCCAUCAUUUCAAACGUAACAGUAACAAGUGUUACACUUCCAAAUGCUGUUUCAACAUUACAAAGUUCCAAACCCAAGACUGAAACUCAGAGUUCAAUUAAAACAACAGAAAUACCAGGUAGUGUUCUACAACCAGAUGCAUCACCUUCUAAAACUGGUACAUUAACCUCAAUACCAGUUACAAUUCCAGAAAACACCUCACAGUCUCAAGUAAUAGGCACUGAGGGUGGAAAAAAUGCAAGCACUUCAGCAACCAGCCGGUCUUAUUCCAGUAUUAUUUUGCCGGUGGUUAUUGCUUUGAUUGUAAUAACACUUUCAGUAUUUGUUCUGGUGGGUUUGUACCGAAUGUGCUGGAAGGCAGAUCCGGGCACACCAGAAAAUGGAAAUGAUCAACCUCAGUCUGAUAAAGAGAGCGUGAAGCUUCUUACCGUUAAGACAAUUUCUCAUGAGUCUGGUGAGCACUCUGCACAAGGAAAAACCAAGAACUGACAGCUUGAGGAAUUCUCUCCACACCUAGGCAAUAAUUACACACUCAGAAAUUUCUUGUAGAAUAAAUGGUACCUGCUGUGCUUGUCUGACCAGUAGCAGAAGACAGAGACAGAGGAGUGCCAUCCAAACAUAUGUGUCAGUAUCAGAAUUUUAUCCCUCUCUAGCCAGUAAUUAGGGAUGGAUUAGGAAUCUUGGAAUUUGUGCACCUCCAGCAUGCUGCAGUGCCCUAUGGAAAAGAGGCAAGACUGCCUUCCCCUGCCCUCCUGCUCUUCACCAGUCAUGAGCCCCUAGCUUGGGCCUGCAAUGCAACCACCUUUCCCCAGCUGAUUAUUCUAAUUGGCAGUGGCUCUGAGUGGCAUGCCAAGGUCCCUGCCCCUGCUGCCACCAAGCUGGGGAGAGAGAAAAAAUCCUAAGCUUGUCUCAGGCCUGCAGUGCACAGUCUGGGAGUGCUAAGCUGAGAUCUAUGACCAGCACUUGAGUGGGAGAGGAUCACACACUCUCAGAGCACUGAGGGGAAGCAUGGCUACAAAUGUGAGGAAACACAGAGGGGCUGCAUGGCUGGGUAAGAGCCUAUCUACCAGUCAUUAUGUUUAAGCACUAUCUAUUAAAUUGCAAACCAAACUUCAACACCAAAAAUACUUUGGUAAUAUACUCCUCUGUAAAACCAAGGACAAGAACUCAACUGCAAAUAAAGACCCUGCACAAAGCCUCAGCCCUCUGAACACAUACAGAAAUGAAACCGACUGACUAUACUCAAAUUACACUGCAAUUAAAGAAACAUCAGUCCACAUAGGUGAGAAAGAACCAGCUCAAGAACUCCUGAAACUCUAAAAGCCAGAUUGCCUCCUUACCUCCAAAUGACUGAACUAGCUGCUCUGCAGUGAUUCUUAACCAGAAUAAAAUGGAUGAAAUUACAGAAAUAGAAUUCAGAAUCUGGAUGGCAAUGAAGAUCACUGAAAAUCAGAAGAUUGAAACCCAUUCCGAGGAAUCUGAGGAAUUCAACAAAACCAUACAAGGAAUGAAAUAUGAAAUAGCCAUUUUAAGAAAGAACAAAACUGAUCUGACAGAGCUGAAAAACUCACCACAAGAAUUUCAUAACACAUUGGAAGUAUUAACAGCAGAGUAGACCAAGUCAAGUAAAGAAUCUCAGAACUCAAAGACUAGUUCUUCACAUUAACAGUCAGAUAAAAAUAAAGAAAAUAGAAUUUUCAAAAAUGAACAAAUCUCCAAGAAACAUGAGAUUAUGUAAAAAGACAAAACUUAUGACCCAUUGGCAUCCCUGAAAGACAGGGAAAGAAAGCAAGCAAUUUGGAAAACAUGUUUGAGGAUAUUGUCCAUGAAAAUGUCCCCAACUUAGCUAGAGAGGUUGAUAUUCAAAUUCAGGAAAUUCAGAGAACCCCAGCAAGAUACUAUAUAAUACAACCAUCCCCAAGACACAUAGUCAUCAGAUCCUCCAAGGUCAAUGUGAAAAGAAAACUAUUAAAGGUAGCUAGGGAGAAUGAGCAGGUCAACCUACAAAGGGAACCACAGCAGUGGAUAACACUGGACCUUUCAGCCAAAACUCUACAAGCCAGAAGAGACUGGGGGCCUAUAUUCAGCAUCCUUAAAGAAAAGAAAUUCCAACAAAGAAUUUCAUAUCCAGCCAAACUAGACCUCAUAAGCAAAGGAGAAAUAAAAUCCUUUUCAGACAAGCAAAUACUAAGGGAAUUCAUUACCACCAGACCUGCUUUUCAAGAGGUUCAUAGGGAGUGCUGAAUAUGGAAAUGAAAGACCAUUACUGGCUACUACAAAAACACACUAAAGUUCAUACACCAUUGAUGCUAUAAAGCAAAAACACAAUCAUGUCUACGUAACGCCAGGUAACAACAGAAUGACAGGAUCAAAUCCACACAUAUUAAUAUUAACCUUGAAUGGUAGUGGGCUAAACACUCCACUUAAAAGGCAUAAAGUGGCAAAUUGAUUAAAGAAGAAAGACCCAAGUGUAUGCUGUCUUUAAGAGACCAAUCUCACAUUCAAGGACACCUAUAGGCUCAGAGUAAAGGGAUGGAGAAAGAUUUAUCAAGCAAAUAGAAAACAAACAAAAAAGAGCAGGGGUUGCUAUUCUUAUUUCAGACAAAACAGACUUUAAACCAAAAAUGAUCAAAAAGGACAAAGAAAGGAAGUGAUAAAGGGUUCAACUCAACAAGAAGACUUAACUAUCCUAAAUAUAUGCACCCAAUACUACAGCACCUGGAUUUAUAAAACAAAUUCUUUUAGUCUUACAAAGAGACAUAGGUAACCACACAAUAAUAGUAGAUUUCAACACCCCACUGAUGAUAUUGGAGAGAUCAUCAAGACAGAUUACUAACAAAGACAUCUGGGACCUACAUUUGACAAUUGACAAAAUAGAACUAACAUGCAUCUACAGAAAAGUCCACUCAACAAAAGCAGAAUAUAAAUCCUUCUCAUCCAUGCAUGACACAUACUCUAAAAUUGACUACAUGCUCAGCCAGAAAUUCUCAAUAAUUUCAAAAAAGCCAAAAUCAUACCAGCCACAUUCUCCGACCACAGCACAAUAAGAGUAGAAAUCAAUACCAAGAAGAUUUUUAAAAACCCUACAACUAAGUGGAUAUUAAAUAAUCUGCUCCUGAAUGACUUUUGUGUAAACAAUGAAAUUAAAGCAGAAAUUAUGAAAUUCUUUAAAACUAAUGAAAGCAAAUAUACAACAUACCAGAAUCUCUGAGAUACAGCUUCAACAGUGUUAAGACAAAAGUUAAUAGCACUAAAUGCCCACAUCAAAAAAUCAGAAAGAUCUCAAAUUGACAAUCUAACAUCACACCUAGAGGAACUAAACAAAUAAGAACAAACUAAUCCCACAGCUAGCAAAAGAAAAAUAACCAAAAUCAGAGAUGAAUUGAGUGACAUGGAGAUGAUAAGAACUAUGCAAAAGAUCAACAAAACCAAAAGUUUGCCUUUUGGAAGAAUAAAUAAGACUGAUAGACUGUUAGCUAGACUAAAAAUGAAAAAAGAGAAGAUCCAAAUAAACACUAUCAGAAAUGAUAGUGGAUAUUACCACUGACUCCACAGAAAUACAAAAACAAACAAACAAACAAAAAAUCCAGAGACUAUUACAAACAUCUUUAUGUACCCAAACCAGAAAACCUAAAAGAAAUAGAUAAAUUCCUGGAAAAAUACAACGUCCCAAGAUUGAACCAGGAAUAAAUUGAAACCCUGAACAGACCAAUAAUGCAUUCCAAAAUUGAAUCAGUAAUAAAAAAACCCUACCAACCAGAAAAAGCCCUGGACCAGACAGAUUCACAGCUGAAUUCUACCAGGUGUACAAAGAAGAGCUGGUACCAAUCCUACUGAAUCAAUUCCAAAAAAACGAGAAGAAACUCCUCCCUAACUCUUUCUAUGUGGCUAACAUCACACUGAUAUCAUGAAACCUGCAGAAACACAAUGAACAAAGAAAACUUCAGGCCAAUAUCUCUGAUGAACCUAGAUGCAAAAGUUCUCAACAAAAUACUAGUAAAGUAAACUGAACCCAGAAGAAUGUCAUAAAGCUAAUCCACCAUGAUCAAGAAAGCUUCAUCCCUGAGAUGCAAGGUUGAUUCAACAUACAUAAAUCAAUAAGUGCAAUUCAUUACAUAAACAGAACUCAAAACAAAAAUUGCAUGAUCAUCUUAAUAAGUGCAGUCAGAAAAGGCUUGUGAAAGAAUUUAACAUCUUUUCAUGUUAAAAUCCCUCAACAAUCCAGGCAUUGAAGAAAUAUACCUCAAAAUAAUAAGAUCCAUCUAUGACAAACCCACAACCAACAUCAGACUGAAUGGGAAAAAGCAUCUGGAAUUGUUCCUGGGAAAACUGUAACAAAACAUGGAUGCCCAGUCUCACCACUCAUAUUCACAUGGUAUUGGGAGUCAUAGCCAGAGCAGUCAGGCAAGAGAAGAAAUAAAAGGCAUUCAAAUAUGAAGAGAAGAAGUUAAACGAUCUGUCUUCAUAGAUUAUAUGUUUCUAUACCUAGAAAACCCCAUAGUCUCUUCCCAAAGGCUCCUAGCUCUGAUAAACAACUUCAGCAAAGUUUUGGGAUACAAAAUCAAUGUACAAAAUUCAGUAGCAUUUCUAUACACCAACAACAUCCAAGCUGAGAGACAAAUCAAGAAUGCAAUCUGAUUCACAGGAGCCACAAAAAGAAUAAAAUACCUAGGAAUAUAGUUAACCUGGAAGACAAAAGAGCUCUAUAAUGAGAAGUACAAAACACUGUCAAAAGAAAUCAGAAAUGACAUGAACCAAUGGAAAAACAUUGCAUGUUCAUGGAUUGGAAGAAUCAAUAUUGUUAAAAAAGGCCAUACUCUUCAAAGCAAUCUACAGAAUCAAUGUUAUUCUCUAUCAAACUACCAGUGACAUUUUUCACAGAAUUAGAAAAAAGCUAUUCUGAAAUUCAUCUGGAUCCAAAAGAGAGCCCAAAUAGCUAAAGCAAUGCUAAGCAAAAAGAACAAAGCUGGAGGCAUUACCUUACCCAACUUCAAAUGAUACUACAAGGCUACAGUAACUAGUACAGUAUGAUACUGAUACAAAAACAGACACACAGAUAAAUGAAACAAGUUAGAGAGCCCUGAAAUAAUGCCACACACCUACAACUUCAAAUGAUACUACAAGGCUACAGUAACUAGUACAGUAUGACAAAUGAUACUACAACUCUACAGUAACUAGUACAGUAUGAUACUGGUACAAAAACAGACAAAUAGAUCAAUGAAACAAGUUAGAGAACUCUGAAAUAAUGCCACACACGUAUAACCAUCUCAUCUUUAACAAAGCUGACAAUAACAAGCAGUGGGGAAAGGACUUUCUAUUCAAGGAAUAGUGCUGGGAUAAAUGGCUAGCCAUAGGCAGAAGAUUAAAACUGGAUCCUUACCUUUUAUCAUAUACAAAAAUCAACUAAGAUGGAUUGAAGACUUGAAUGUAAAACAAAAACUAUAAAAUCCCUAGAAGAAUACCUAGGAAAUACCAUUCUGUGCAUCAGUCUUCAUGAUGAAGACUCCAAAAGCAAUUGCAACAAAAACAAAAACUAACAAGACCUAGCUAAACUAAAGAGCUUCUGCACAGCCUAAGAAACUAUCAACAGAGUAAACAGACGACUUACAAAAUGGGAGAAAAUGUUCACGAACUAUGCAUCCGAUAAAGGUAUAAUAUCCAGAAUCUAUAAGGAACUUAAACAAAUGAAAGAGUAAAAAACAACCCCAUUAAAAAAUGGGCAAAGGACAUGAAUGCACACUUCUCAAAAGAAGACAUACACAGGGCCAACAAGCAUAUGCAAAAGUGCCUAAUAUCACUAAUCAUUUGGGAAAUGCAAAUCAAAACCAUAAUGAGAUGCUGUCUCAUAUCAGUCAGAAUGGUGACCAUUAAAAAGUCAAGAAGUCACAGAUGCUGGCCAGGUUGUAGAGAAAAGGGAAUGCUUAUACACUGCAGGUGAGAAUGUAAAUGAGUUCAAUCACUGUGGAAACAGCCUGGAGAUUUCUCAAAGAACUUAAAAUAGAACUACCAUUCAACCCAGCAGUCCCAUUACUAGAUACAGACCAAAGAAAUACAAAUUGUUUUACUACCAAAUCACAUGACAUGUAUGUUCAUCACAGCACUAUUUACAAUAAGAGAGACAUGGAAUGAACCUAGAUGCCCACCAACCUAGAUGCCCACCAACCUAGAUGCCCAUCAGUGGUGGACUAGAUAAAGAAAAUGUGGUACGCAUACACUGUGGAAUACUAUGCAGCCAUAUAAGAGAGCCAGAUUGUUACUUUUGCAACAACAUGGAUGAAUCUGGAGUCCAUUAUUCUAAGUGAAGUUACCAAAGAGCAGAAAACCAAAUACUUUAUCUUCGCAUUUCUAAGGGGGUGCCAAGCACUAAAGGCACAAAGCGGGGAACAAGAGACACCAGAGAAUGAGUAUUGAGACACUACCUAUUUGGUAUUAUGCCAAUUACAUGGAUGAUAAAAUGGUCUGAACGCCAAACCCCUAUGACGUGCAAUGCCCAUGUAACCAACCUCCAGAUGUACCCCUUGAAACUAAAAUAAAAGUUUUAAAGGAAAAAAAAGGAACCUGGAAGUUGGUCCAUCCUAUGCAAUGGACACUUUCAGGUGCAAAGUUUGAGAAGAUGAGGAUGAGAGACGUUGUCCAGCCCUAGCUGAUAUAUGGAAACCUUCCUUUCUACUUGCUAUGGUUGCUUUGCAACCCAGUGGCUAGUAAAGGGCUGUUUUUUAAAUUACCAAAAUGCUCAAAUAUUAGUAACUAAUUGUCCAACUUGGAAAAAGCAAGUCUUCUGCAGUUGGAAAAAAAAGAAAAAAGAAAGAAAGAAAAGGUAUAUAGAAGGCAAGGAACAGUGUUGAUCUUCGAACCAGCUUAAUAAAAGUAAUUUUUGUUCAACUCCCAUUCCUUUCCAUUUCUGUACUUUAAAAAAUAUUCCUAGCCUCAGAUUCCAAGCCUUUUGAUUUGAAAAGCUAAAUAACUUUUAUUGCUCCUUUUUGUAAUUUUGGAAUUAUAUAAUGAUGUUCUGAAGAGUAAAGAUCAGAAAGUAAUGGGAAGAAACAAGUUUGACAUCUGUUCAAUUCUAUUGUCUGUCUCACUUUUUUCCUUAAGAUAUUUCUAUCACUGUACUUUGAAUUUAAUAACCAAAGAGUAACUACUAUCUAGGUUGUCAACUUGAAAUUAGAUAUCAACUUGGAGAUUCAGAAUAUAUAGAAAUGAAUUCAUCAAACCUAGAAGAUUUCAGGAAAGAAGUUAAAAAGUCUUGAACCCUCAUGAAACAGCAAACAGUAAUACAGAAAUCAUCACCUAUGUUAAAAAUUUCCAUAUCAAAACAAGAUUUUAGAUAUAUUUAAUGCUUGUUGCUUCAUAUAUUGAUCAUCUAUUUAGUGCACAGUAUUAUGUUUAAUGUGAUUCGGCAGGGCAGACAGGAAUUUUGAAACAUUUAUGAGCUAUAAACCUUGCCUUCUGCAAAGCUUUACUUCGUGGGAGCAUGAAAUCAUAUACAAGAGGGGUAGCAAAUACGUAGAAGCAGCUUAAAUGUUUAAUGAUAUGGAAAUUAUAAAAUAAAUUAUACUUUGCACAGUGACAUUAUAUAAUGAGUAAAAAUAAUUCUCGAAAUAAUUUUUAAUAACAUGAAAGCAUGUCUAAGAUAUAAAAUUAAAAGGGAAAAAUAACAACUUUAGAAUUGAACAGAUAGCCAUUUAACUGUUCUAUGACCAACUCUGCACUGUUGUCAAGGGGGAAUCUGCUGCUACCUGGUUGCUCCCUCACCAGUAGGUCUCAUCUUCCUUCUGUUCCAAGACACCUUUGAAGGCUGAAGAGUGAAGGGGGUUUCAGACCAGUGAAGAACUGUGGUGUUAGAAAGUCCGGUAGCUUGGAUCAAAGUCCGUUCCCACAGACCCUCAGCAAUGUGGAUUGUUAGCUAUUUCCAUUUUUCUCCAAGAUACAAUUCCCUGAUACUUCUGUAAUUUUCUUAAUGGUGCCCUGAUAAUCUGGGAGUAGCUUUGUGAACUUCCAGAAGAGCUUAACAUGUUUUUCAAUUAUUUUUCUUUCAUUUUAAAAUAAAAUAACACAAGCUAAAAGGAAAACAUCAUAAAUAAAGGAUAUUUACAAUUGCCUCUCUGUAUUCAUGGAGGUGGAAGAUUGAUUUCAAAAGGCCUGGAGAUACCAAAAUCUGUGGUUGCUCAAGUCCCUGAUGUAAAUAAAACUGCAUAGUAUUUGAAUAUAACCUA